GUUCCCGGCCGGGAGCGACCCGGAGUCCCCAGCCCCGCGUCCCAGCUGCCGCCAGCGCCAGUUUUGGAUUCGGCGGAUUAGGAAGAGGAGGGAGGGGGGAGAGAGCGCGAAGAGGGAGGGGACCGAAGCUGGAGGGUCCCGAGUCCAGCGCCGUGUUGGCGUAGAGAAACUUUCCCUCUCGGCCUCGGAGACGGCGCCCCGGCCGUGCCGGAGUGGAGAUCGCCAGGCUCGGAGGAACCGGCAGCUCUCCACGCCCCUGCCCGAAGCCUGACCCGACUGCCUCUCUCAGUGAGGUACGGAGAUUUAUCUAGGCUCUUCCCUGGCUGCGAACCCAGGCUCCCUCCAGGUAGCGUGGAAUCGCUUAGAAGCUGAUAUCCCGAGGGGCGGUGGGGGUGGACAGCUCCGGCCACCAGUGCCCGGGAAGGAGGGCGCGGGGCUGCGCGUAGCCGCUGGCCAGCAGGUUGUAAAAAAUUAGGACAGCUAAAUGCUCAGGGAGUCGUCCAGCACUAAAGGAGGCUAAGACCUGUUGACGCCUGCUAUGGCAGCGCUUGAGAAAUGACUGGGGGAGUCCAGCGAGGUCGGGGACGCAGCGGUCUCCGGGCUCCAGAAACCUCCUUAGCCUUUUGUGGUAACUUUGGUCCGGCGGCGGGGGGCCGGUGAGCAGGAACUGGAGGGAGGCGGUGGGGAAACCGUGGAUCCGUCCGGCUGAGGGUGCGUGGAUCAGACUGGGCUGAGCAGUUAUUUAUGAUUCCAUCUGAUAUACAUAGGAGAGAAACUGAUAGAAGAAUUCUGAUGGCAACUGUAUGAUAGAAGCUAUAUAAAGUCAAGUGUCCAUUUUCUUUCAACUAUAUUUGAGCAUACCCAGGAUUUAAGUCGUGGAACUGAACAUUUAUUUGGCUGAUCCUCAUCAUGAACCGUGCUUUUAGCAGGAAGAAAGACAAAACAUGGAUGCAUACACCUGAAGCUUUAUCAAAACAUUUCAUUCCCUAUAAUGCAAAGUUUCUUGGCAGUACAGAAGUGGAACAGCCAAAAGGAACAGAAGUUGUGAGAGAUGCUGUAAGGAAACUAAAGUUUGCAAGACAUAUCAAGAAAUCUGAAGGCCAGAAAAUUCCUAAAGUGGAGUUGCAAAUAUCAAUUUAUGGAGUAAAAAUUCUAGAACCCAAAACAAAGGAAGUUCAACACAAUUGCCAGCUUCAUAGAAUAUCUUUUUGUGCAGAUGAUAAAACUGACAAGAGGAUAUUCACUUUCAUAUGCAAAGAUUCUGAGUCAAAUAAACAUUUGUGCUAUGUAUUUGACAGCGAAAAGUGUGCUGAAGAGAUCACUUUAACAAUUGGCCAAGCAUUUGACCUGGCAUACAGGAAAUUUCUAGAAUCAGGAGGAAAAGAUGUUGAAACAAGAAAACAGAUCGCAGGGUUACAAAAAAGAAUCCAAGACUUAGAAACAGAAAAUAUGGAACUUAAAAAUAAAGUACAAGAUUUGGAAAACCAACUGAGAAUAACUCAAGUAUCAGCACCUCCACUGCUGCACAAUAUGUCUGAUCAUGAACAACAUGUGUUUCAGAGAUGCUCAUCCUCUUUCUGGCGUAGUAAUGGUGAUUCAUCUCCCUGUCUCAAUAUUUCUUCCAUCUCUGUCACUCCUAUCAACUCGCCUGAUUCCAGACUAUCACUGGGACUGUUAAUACCACCACCUUCUAAAUGUGGCUUUCCCAAGCCAGUCAGUGAGAGCAGCAUCCCAAGACCUCAUGCAGGCAGUAUGACACCUAAGUCGCCCUCCACUGACAUCUUUGAUAUGAUUCCAUUUUCUCCAAUAUCACACCAGUCUUCGAUGCCUACUCGCAAUGGCACACAGCCACCUCCAGUACCUAGUAGAUCUACUGAGAUUAAACGGGACCUGUUUGGAGCAGAACCUUUUGACCCAUUUAACUGUGGAGCAGCAGAUUUCCCUCCAGAUAUUCAAUCAAAAUUAGAUGAGAUGCAGCGCCAGAGAUGGAGGGGUUCAAAAUGGGACUAACUCUUGAAGGCACAGUAUUUUGUCUCGACCCGUUAGACAGUAGGUGCUGACAUCAAGAACAAGAAAUCCUGAUUCAUGUUAAAUGUGUUUGUAUACACAUGUCAUUUAUUAUUAUUACUUUAAGAUAGGUAUUAUUCAUGUGUCAAUGUUUUUGAAUAUUUUAAUAUUUUGAAAAUUUUCUCAGUUAAAUUUCCUCACCUUCACUAUUGAUCUGUAAUUUUUAUUUUAAAAACAGCUUACUGUAAAGUAGAUCAUACUUUUAUGUUCCUUUCUGUUUCUACUGUAGAUGAAUUUGUAAUUGAAAGACAUAUUAUACAAAUACCUGCCUUGUGUCUGAGUUCUAUUUAGUUAGCAUCUUGAAAUUUGUAUUCAUUUUCCAGAUGGCUAGUUUAUUAAUGAUUUCCCAAAAGCCAUACCUUAAAGAUAACUUUUUAAAUUCUGAAGAGACAUGCCAAUGUCAAACUAAACAUGUUCUGUUUUUAAACCAACAAACAUGUUACUAUUCAUUGGACAGAUAUCAUUUUAUGUAUAAAUACUGUUCACAUCACUGGGAAAAUGUAAACUUUAAACAUAAUGCCACAAGGUCACUAAUUUCUAGCAGGUAAAAUUAUAAGGAUAUAAAUUCCAAUAAUAAACCAAAUGUAUUUAGAGUAUUUAUUAGUAAAUGCAAGGUGAUGUUAGUUAUGAUCAGUUAUACUCUAAAUAUUUAAUUUGUUUUAUAAAGGUAGUGAAAAAAUGAAAAUUUGCUAUUUAUUAAAAAACAUUAAAUUUCAUUCCAAAUGAGAUAAGUGAUAUUACUAUAACAUCUAAGCAUCAUCUGAUUUGAUAUUCCCUAAAAAACAUUUGGAAUAUAUGCUAUCUAUAGAUUCAGUAUCUACUACCCAUAUUUACUUUACCAAAUAUAUUUCUCCUCACUGCAUAAGGACUACUCUUCUCAUAUUUUCUUCUUUGAUGAAGAUAUUUUUCACCAAAGUUUAUUUUGUGAUGCCCUCUUGGUUUUGAUACUUUAAAAUCUGUGGCACCCGUUCUACAUGAAUUAUCAAUAUUUGGUAAAUUCAAUCUGUAUUUGUUUUGUUAAAGUCAAAAAUCUCAUUUUCCAAAAAAAAAAAAAAAACCCAGUUACUGCUCAGUUUAGUCUUGAACAUGAGCAAUAAAAUUCUCUUGCAUUUCAUUAUUGAUGUGCUGAUGAACCUGGACUUUUAAAAAUAUUUGUUUCCUAUACCUUUACCCUUUACCUAACAGACUAAUUUGUACUCAGUAAAACAAAAAUUUAUGGUCAAAAUUUCUAACUUGGUUCAUCACAUUAUAAGAUAAAUAAAUUAAAUUAAUGAAAAUGUGACUUAGAGUAGGGGUAGCCCUCAAAAAUAGAUUUAUCAUUUACUCAUUGGAAUUUUCUUCAAGUGUUAAAGGUACAUUUUCACUAGGAAAAGAAAUCAAAUAUGCUUAUGCAAUAUAUAUUUGUGUGUUUUUCCUUAAUGUUAUAUGGUAUAUAUGAGCCUUCUUGUUUAGUUUCUUUUAUCUGCUAAGUUGUACCUUAAUUAGAGGGCAAUAUAUGUUUCAUAAAGAAGAGUCUUUAUAAUUUUGUUUGUCAGAUAGUAUUUUGGAAUUUGUAUAAUAAGGAUGUUUAGAAGCCAUAUAAGUGGCUUUUUUUAACAGAUAGAAUUUGUAUUUUUAUUGUACUUUAAAAAGAUUUAUGUAAUAGGUAUAUAUUUAGUGGCCAUUUAUUAUCAAUGGUAACACAAUGGAGUACUAAGAUGGUAUUUGCACAUUUAAGAUAUGUUACUUUACCAAUUUUUAAUGGUAAUCAACUCUGCUACUGGCAUGAUGAAAUAGUACAUAACUGGUCAUUAAUUAUGAACAUUUAUUUCUCCAGUGCGUUUUUAUGAAGAUCUGGUUGAAAAUUGUAUUUCUAUGUAAACUCAACGAUAUGUUUGGUUUUCCUGAAAAUAAAUGAUUUUAAAUAAA